AAGCCCCUGCAGGGAGCGGGCCCGGGCGGCGCGCGAUCGAGGUCGGGUCGCCGUCCAGCCUGCAGCAUGAGCGCCCCCAGCGCGACCCCCAUCUUCGCGCCCGGCGAGAACUGCAGCCCCGCGUGGGGGGCGGCGCCCGCGGCCUACGACGCAGCGGACACGCACCUGCGCAUCCUGGGCAAGCCGGUGAUGGAGCGCUGGGAGACCCCCUAUAUGCACGCGCUGGCCGCCGCCGCCUCCUCCAAAGGGGGCCGGGUCCUGGAGGUGGGCUUUGGCAUGGCCAUCGCAGCGUCAAAGGUGCAGGAGGCGCCCAUUGAUGAGCAUUGGAUCAUCGAGUGCAAUGACGGCGUCUUCCAGCGGCUCCGGGACUGGGCCCCACGGCAGACACACAAGGUCAUCCCCUUGAAAGGCCUGUGGGAGGAUGUGGCACCCACCCUGCCUGACGGUCACUUUGAUGGGAUCCUGUACGACACGUACCCACUCUCGGAGGAGACCUGGCACACACACCAGUUCAACUUCAUCAAGAACCACGCCUUUCGCCUGCUGAAGCCGGGGGGCGUCCUCACCUACUGCAACCUCACCUCCUGGGGGGAGCUGAUGAAGUCCAAGUACUCAGACAUCACCAUCAUGUUUGAGGUGCGCCCACCUGAAGUUCCCCAUGGGUCUCCAGGAAGUGACCUUGGAUGGGGGUGGGAAGGGGCUGCUGGAGCCACCUUGCUACCUGGGGAGGGUCCCUUCCUGACCCCCUGGGUGGGCUGGACUGUGCUGGUUCAUUUAGAAAUCAAAGUCCUUUGCCUGGCGCAGUGGCUGCCAGGAGCAGUGGCUCAGGUCUAUAAUCCCAGCACUGUGGAAGGCCGAGGUGGGCAGAUUGCUUGAGCCUAGGAGUUCAAGACCAGCCUGGGCUACAGAGCAAGACCUCAUCUUUCCUAAAAAAAAAAAAUACAAAAAACUAGCUGGGCGUGGUGGCGUGUGCCUGUACUCCCAGCUACUUGGGAGGCUGAGGUAGGAGGAUUGCUUGGGCCCCAGGGGCAGAGGUUGCAGUGAGCCCAGAUCGAACCACUGCACUCCAGCCUGGGUAACAGAGCCAGACCCUGUCUCAAGAAAAAAGAAAGAAAGAAAGAAAGAAAGAAAAUUUAAAAAAAAAAUGGAAAUCAGGCUGGGCGUGGUGGCUCACACCUGUGAUCCCGGCACUUCGGAAGGCCAAGGCGGGUGGAUCACUUGAGCCCAGGAGUUUGAGCCUAGCCUGGCCAACAUGGCAGAAUCCCAUCUCUACUAAAAAUACAAAAGUUAGCCAGGCGUGGUGGCGGGCGCCUGUAAUUCCAGCUACUCGGGAGGCUGAGGCAUGAGAAUCACUUGAACAUGGGAGGCGGAGGUUGCUGUGAGCCGAGAUUGCACCGUUGUACUCCAGCCUGGGCAACAGACCGAGACUCCAUCUCAACAAAACAAAAACAAAAAAAAUGGAAAUCAAAGUCCCUCACCAGCUCAACAACCUCCCAUGGCUCCCCAGUGCCCUGUGGUUCAGCCUAAGCCCUGCGUGUUCCCCUCCCUCCAGCUGCCUCCACCUGGCUGUCUUUGCUGGUUCAGCAGUGCUUGUCUCGCUGUUCCCUCUGCCUGGUGGAGGCGGCCUAUCUGAGAAGGGCUCUAUGUGGUUGCCCUGGGCUGCUGUUGUGAGAGCCGGCUGGGUGCCUGUGGCCCCUGGGGCAGCUUUUCUUCCAAAAUGGGAACUAGUGGCCUGUG